AGUCCCAUCAAGCCUGCUCCUAGGAAGAGAGCUGGUUUUUUUUUCCUCCUCCUUCCACUCUUAGGACAUGCCUGAUCUUCUUGAGCAGUCCAGCACAAGCUAAUCCACAAGGUUCAAUCAGGCUAAGUAAUUGGAGGAAUGUGUUAACUCUGAAUUACAAGGAGCAGAAGGGAAGGAUCUGUCAGCUGACUAAUCAGGGAUAGUGGUUUUUUUUUUUUUUUCCUCCCCAGCAUUGCUGCCACUGUGCUAAUGGAAGCAGCCACGGCAGCUUUGUUUGAUAGAGAUUUUUGGCUGCCGUUUUUAAAUACUACCCAAGAAGCAGCUCGUAUUUCAUCAACGUUGCGUUGACAAUUGGAAAAGAAAAGUGUAAUUGCGUACAGGCGAAAUGGCAGAAGCAAAUCCCCGGAGAGGCAAGAUGAGGUUCAGAAGGAAUGCGGCUUCCUUCCCUGGGAACUUGCACUUGGUUUUGGUUUUACGUCCUACCAGCUUUCUUCAACGAACGUUCACAGACAUUGGAUUUUGGUUUAGUCAGGAGGAUUUUAUGCUUAAAUUACCAGUUGUUAUGCUGAGCUCAGUUAGUGAUUUGCUGACAUACAUUGAUGACAAGCAAUUAACCCCUGAGUUAGGCGGCACCUUGCAGUACUGCCACAGUGAAUGGAUCAUCUUCAGAAAUGCUAUAGAAAAUUUUGCCCUCACAGUGAAAGAAAUGGCUCAGAUGUUACAGUCCUUUGGAACUGAACUGGCUGAGACAGAACUACCAGAUGAUAUUCCCUCAAUAGAAGAAAUUCUGGCAAUUCGUGCUGAAAGGUAUCAUCUGUUGAAGAAUGAUAUUACAGCUGUAACCAAAGAAGGAAAAAUUCUGCUAACAAAUCUGGAAGUGCCUGACACUGAAGGAGCUGUCAGUUCAAGACUAGAAUGUCAUCGGCAAAUAAGUGGUGACUGGCAAACUAUUAAUAAGUUGCUGACUCAAGUACAUGAUAUGGAAACAGCUUUUGAUGGAUUUUGGGAAAAACAUCAAUUAAAAAUGGAGCAGUAUCUGCAACUAUGGAAGUUUGAGCAGGAUUUUCAACAGCUUGUGACUGAAGUUGAAUUUCUAUUAAACCAACAAGCAGAACUGGCUGAUGUAACAGGGACUAUAGCUCAAGUAAAACAAAAAAUAAAAAAAUUGGAAAACUUAGAUGAAAAUUCUCAGGAGCUAUUAUCAAAGGCCCAGUUUGUGAUAUUACAUGGACACAAGCUUGCAGCAAAUCACCAUUAUGCACUUGAUUUAAUCUGCCAGAGGUGCAAUGAGCUACGUUACCUUUCUGAUAUUUUGGUUAAUGAGAUAAAAGCAAAACGGAUACAACUCAGCAGGACCUUCAAAAUGCAUAAACUCCUACAGCAGGCUCGUCAAUGCUGUGAUGAAGGGGAAUGUCUUCUAGCUAAUCAGGAAAUAGAUAAGUUUCAGUCUAAAGAAGAUGCUCAGAAAGCUCUCCAAGACAUUGAAAAUUUUCUUGAAAUGGCUCUACCCUUUAUAAAUUAUGAACCUGAAACACUGCAGUAUGAAUUUGAUGUAAUAUUAUCUCCUGAGCUUAAGGUUCAAAUGAAGACUAUACAACUCAAGCUUGAAAACAUUCGAAGUAUAUUUGAGAACCAGCAGGCUGGUUUCAGGAACCUGGCAGAUAAGCAUGUGAGGCCAAUCCAAUUUGUGGUACCCACACCUGAAAAUUUGGUCACAUCUGGGACACCAUUUUUUUCAUCUAAACAAGUGGGAGUUGGAUACUCUUUCUUUCAAGCAUGUAAACUUUUUUCAAAAGGGAAGAAGACUUGGAGACAAAAUCAGAGCAACUUAAAAAUUGAAGUGGUGCCUGAUUGUCAGGAGAAGAGAAGUUCUGGUCCAUCCUCCAGUUUGGACAAUGGCAAUAGCUUGGAUGUUUUAAAGAACCACGUACUAAAUGAACUGAUACAGACUGAGAGAGUUUAUGUUCGAGAACUGUAUACUGUUUUGUUGGGUUAUAGAGCGGAGAUGGAUAAUCCAGAGAUGUUUGAUCUUAUGCCACCUCUCCUGAGAAAUAAAAAGGACAUUCUCUUUGGAAACAUGGCAGAAAUAUAUGAAUUCCAUAACGACAUUUUCUUGAGCAGCCUGGAAAAUUGUGCUCAUGCUCCAGAAAGAGUGGGACCUUGUUUCCUGGAAAGGAAGGAUGAUUUUCAGAUGUAUGCAAAAUAUUGUCAGAAUAAGCCCAGAUCAGAAACAAUUUGGAGGAAGUAUUCAGAAUGCGCAUUUUUCCAGGAAUGUCAAAGAAAGUUAAAACACAGACUUAGACUGGAUUCCUAUUUACUCAAACCAGUGCAACGAAUCACUAAAUAUCAGUUAUUGUUGAAGGAGCUAUUAAAAUAUAGCAAAGACUGUGAAGGAUCUGCUCUGUUGAAGAAGGCACUCGAUGCAAUGCUGGAUUUACUGAAGUCAGUUAAUGAUUCUAUGCAUCAGAUUGCAAUAAAUGGCUAUAUUGGAAACUUAAAUGAACUGGGCAAGAUGAUAAUGCAAGGUGGAUUCAGCGUUUGGAUAGGGCACAAGAAAGGUGCUACAAAAAUGAAGGAUUUGGCUAGAUUCAAACCAAUGCAGCGACACCUUUUCUUGUAUGAAAAAGCCAUUGUUUUUUGCAAAAGGCGUGUUGAAAGUGGAGAAGGCUCUGACAGAUACCCGUCAUACAGUUUUAAACACUGUUGGAAAAUGGAUGAAGUUGGAAUCACUGAAUAUGUAAAAGGUGAUAACCGCAAGUUUGAAAUCUGGUAUGGUGAAAAGGAAGAAGUUUAUAUUGUCCAGGCUUCUAAUGUAGAUGUGAAGAUGACGUGGCUAAAAGAAAUAAGAAAUAUUUUGUUGAAGCAGCAGGAACUUUUGACAGUUAAAAAAAGAAAGCAACAGGAUCAAUUAACAGAACGGGAUAAGUUUCAGAUUUCUCUUCAGCAGAAUGAUGAAAAGCAACAGGGAGCUUUUAUAAGUACUGAGGAAACUGAAUUGGAACACACCAGCACUGUGGUGGAGGUCUGUGAGGCAAUUGCGUCAGUUCAGGCAGAAGCAAAUACAGUUUGGACUGAGGCAUCACAAUCUGCAGAAAUCUCUGAAGAACCUGCGGAAUGGUCAAGCAACUAUUUCUACCCUACUUAUGAUGAAAAUGAAGAAGAAAAUAGGCCCCUCAUGCUAUGGUAUCAGAAGAUAAAGUAAAUAUGCAAAAUUGAAGAAUGCUUUAAUCACAGAGGAUGGGAAUAUAGAAAAACCUAUUAGUUUCUCUCUCUUUGUCCAAUAAUUCUCUGAGAUGUGCUACUAAGGAAAACAUAUAAAAGAGCAACACAAUGUAUUCCAUACACCCUUCUUCCCUGCCAAAACAAGAAGCUGGAAUGACCUGCUCUUUUGGCUUCACUUGGUCAAGUUGUAAACUGAGCAAUAAUGGGUGCUGCUUCCCUUGUAGAGACCUGUGUCGGAGAUGGCUCUCCUAUAUUGAUGAAGCUACUAUGUCAAAUGGCAAGUAGCUCUUUCCUGCCUGCUUCUCAGCUCAUUUGGAAAAAUACUGCGCAAAAGACAUUGAGCUCAAAUGAUGCAGAUGUUGUUUUCAGGUUAAUGGACACGCAAAGAAACCACAGCACAUACUUCUUUUCUUUCAUUUAAUAAAGCUUUUAAUUAUGGUACGCUGUCUUUUUAAAAUCAUGUAUUUAAUGUGUCAGAUAUUGUGCUUGAAAGAUUCUCAUCUCAGAAUACUUUUGGACUUGAAAAUUAUUUCUUCUCUACUUUGUAACCAAAUGCAAUCGGUGUGCCUUGGAUUAUUUAGUUUAUUAAUGAAUUAAGUCAAAAUUACGGCUGCAAAAUGGCUAAGGUCAAGUAAAGCACAACAUUAUGAUUUAAUAUGCUUUUGUUGAAACCACAGCUUUUGUGCCCAUUGUUUUAACUUGUGUGAAACAAUACAAAGCCCAGAAAUUCUUUUCGGGGCAUGAGUAAAUUUUGUUCAGGGCUACUGUCUGUAUGUGCCCAGAUAAAAUUUUCAUGAGAGUAGUUUACAAAAGCCGUAUUUAAAAGUUAAUAUUUUCACACUUUUUUUCUGGAUUUCUGCUUAUAAUUAAUGUAACUUAAAUUAGUUGUGCUCUGCUAUUUUCUGUAUAUUUCAUGUUGUAAUUCUUUUUUUCAAAUAAAAAUUAAUUCUUCAGGUUA